AGAUUCGCUGGACGAUCGCAAGCGCGGAGGCCGGGCGGGCGCGCGCGCCAUGGAGCGGCUGCGGGACGUGCGGGAGCGGCUGCAGGCGUGGGAGCGCGCGUUCCGACGGCAGCGCGGGCGGCGACCGAGCCAGGUGCGGGCUGCCCAGGGGCCGAGGGGCUGAGGGCGCGGCCCGCGGCUGACGCGUUCCCUUUACAGGACGACGUGGAGGCGGCGCCGGAGGAGACCCGCGCGCUCUACCGGGAAUACCGCACUCUGAAGCGUACCACGGGCCAGGCCGGCGGCGGGCUCCGCAGCUCCGAGUCGCUCCCCGCGGCGGCCGAAGAGGCGCCAGAGCCCCGCUGCUGGGGGCCCCAUCUGAAUCGGGCUGCGACCAAGAGUCCACAGUCUACGCCAGGGCGGAGCCGCCAGGGCUCGGUGCCGGACUACGGGCAGCGGCUCAAGGCCAAUCUGAAAGGCACCCUGCAGGCCGGACCAGCCCUGGGCCGCAGACCGUGGCCUCUAGGAAGAGCCUCAUCUAAGGCAUCCACCCCAAAGCCCCCAGGUACAGGGCCUGUCCCCUCCUUUGCAGAAAAAGUCAGUGAUGAGCCUCCACAGCUCCCUGAGCCCCAGCCAAGGCCAGGCCGGCUCCAGCAUCUGCAGGCAUCCCUGAGCCAGCGGCUGGGCUCCCUAGAUCCUGGCUGGUUACAGCGAUGUCACAGUGAGGUCCCAGAUUUUCUGGGGGCCCCCAAAGCCUGCAGGCCUGAUCUAGGCUCAGAGGAAUCACAACUUCUGAUCCCUGGUGAGUCGGCUGUCCUUGGUCCUGGUGCUGGCUCCCAGGGCCCAGAGGCUUCAGCCUUCCAAGAAGUCAGCAUCCGUGUGGGGAGCCCCCAGCCCAGCAGCAGUGGAGGCGAGAAGCGGAGAUGGAACGAGGAGCCCUGGGAGAGCCCCGCACAGGUCCAGCAGGAGAGCAGCCAAGCUGGACCCCCAUCGGAGGGGGCUGGGGCUGUAGCAGUUGAGGAAGACCCUCCAGGGGAACCUGUACAGGCACAGCCACCUCAGCCCUGCAGCAGCCCAUCGAACCCCAGGUACCACGGACUCAGCCCCUCCAGUCAAGCUAGGGCUGGGAAGGCUGAGGGCACAGCCCCCCUGCACAUCUUCCCUCGGCUGGCCCGCCAUGACAGGGGCAAUUACGUACGGCUCAACAUGAAGCAGAAACACUACGUGCGGGGCCGGGCACUCCGUAGCAGGCUCCUCCGCAAGCAGGCAUGGAAGCAGAAGUGGCGGAAGAAAGGGGAGUGUUUUGGGGGUGGUGGUGCCACAGUCACAACCAAGGAGUCUUGUUUCCUGAACGAGCAGUUCGAUCACUGGGCAGCCCAGUGUCCCCGGCCAGCAAGUGAGGAAGACACAGAUGCUGUUGGGCCUGAGCCACUGGUUCCUUCACCACAACCUGUACCUGAGGUGCCCAGCCUGGACCCCACCGUGCUGCCACUCUACUCCCUGGGGCCCUCAGGGCAGUUGGCAGAGACGCCGGCUGAGGUGUUCCAGGCCCUGGAGCAGCUGGGGCACCAAGCCUUUCGCCCUGGGCAGGAGCGUGCAGUCAUGCGGAUCCUGUCUGGCAUCUCCACGCUGCUGGUGCUGCCUACAGGUGCCGGCAAGUCCCUGUGCUACCAGCUCCCAGCGCUGCUCUACAGCCGGCGCAGCCCCUGCCUCACGUUGGUCGUCUCUCCCCUGCUGUCACUCAUGGAUGACCAGGUGUCUGGCCUGCCACCGUGUCUCAAGGCGGCCUGCAUACACUCGGGCAUGACCAGGAAGCAACGGGAAUCUGUCCUGCAGAAGAUUCGGGCAGCCCAGGUACACGUGCUGAUGCUGACACCUGAGGCACUGGUGGGGGCGGGAGGCCUCCCUCCAGCCGCACAGCUGCCUCCAGUUGCUUUUGCCUGCAUUGAUGAGGCCCACUGCCUCUCCCAGUGGUCCCACAACUUCCGGCCCUGCUACCUGCGCGUCUGCAAGGUGCUUCGGGAGCGCAUGGGCGUGCACUGCUUCCUGGGCCUCACAGCCACAGCCACACGCCGCACUGCCAGUGACGUGGCACAGCACCUGGCUGUGGCUGAAGAGCCUGACCUCCACGGGCCAGCCCCAGUUCCCACCAACCUGCACCUUUCCGUGUCCAUGGACAGGGACACAGACCAGGCACUGUUGACGCUGCUGCAAGGCAAACGUUUUCAAAACCUCGAUUCCAUUAUCAUUUACUGCAACCGGCGCGAGGACACAGAGCGGAUCGCUGCGCUCCUCCGAACCUGCCUGCACGCAGCCUGGGUCCCAGGGUCUGGAGGUCGUGCCCCCAAAACCACAGCCGAGGCCUACCACGCGGGCAUGUGCAGCCGGGAACGGCGGCGGGUACAGCGAGCCUUCAUGCAGGGCCAGUUGCGGGUGGUGGUGGCCACGGUGGCCUUUGGGAUGGGGCUGGACCGGCCAGAUGUGCGGGCUGUGCUGCAUCUGGGGCUGCCCCCAAGCUUCGAGAGCUACGUGCAGGCCGUGGGCCGGGCCGGGCGUGACGGGCAGCCUGCCCACUGCCACCUCUUCCUGCAGCCCCAGGGCGAAGACCUGCGAGAGCUGCGCAGACAUGUGCACGCCGACAGCACGGACUUCCUGGCUGUGAAGAGGCUGGUACAGCGCGUGUUCCCAGCCUGCACCUGCACCUGCACCAGGCCGCCCUCGGAGCAGGAAGGGGCCGUGGGUGGGGAGAGGCCUGUGCCCAAGUACCCCCCUCAAGAGGCUGAGCAGCUUAGCCACCAAGCAGCCCCAGGACCCAGAAGGGUCUGCAUGGGCCAUGAGCGGGCACUCCCAAUACAGCUUACCGUACAGGCUUUGGACAUGCCGGAGGAGGGUGAGGAACCUGGGGUAAGCCACAGGGGUGUGGAGGGGCUGUCCCCGCGUCCGCUGAGCCCUGCUCUGCCCCCAGCCAUCGAGACUUUGCUGUGCUACCUGGAGCUGCACCCACACCACUGGCUGGAGCUGCUGGCGACCACCUAUACCCAUUGCCGUCUGAACUGCCCUGGGGGCCCUGCCCAGCUCCAGGCCCUGGCCCACAGGUGUCCCCCUUUGGCUGUGUGCUUGGCCCAGCAGCUGCCUGAGGACCCAGGGCAAGGCAGCAGCUCCGUGGAGUUUGACAUGGUCAAGCUGGUGGACUCCAUGGGCUGGGAGCUGGCCUCUGUGCGGCGGGCUCUCUGCCAGCUGCAGUGGGACCACGAGCCCAGGACAGGUGUGCGGCGUGGGACAGGGGUGCUUGUGGAGUUCAGUGAGCUGGCCUUCCACCUUCGCAGCCCGGGGGACUUGACCGCUGAGGAGAAGGACCAGAUAUGUGACUUCCUCUAUGGCCGUGUGCAGGCCCGGGAGCGCCAGGCCCUGGCCCGUCUGCGCAGAACCUUCCAGGCCUUUCACAGCGUAGCCUUCCCCAGCUGCGGGCCCUGCCUGGAGCAGCAGGAUGAGGAGCGCAGCACCAGGCUCAAGGACCUGCUCGGCCGCUACUUUGAGGAAGAGGAAGGGCAGGAGCCGGGAGGCAUGGAGGACGCACAGGGCCCCGAGCCAGGGCAGGCCAGACUCCAGGAUUGGGAGGACCAGGUCCGCUGCGACAUCCGCCAGUUCCUGUCCCUGAGGCCAGAGGAGAAGUUCUCCAGCAGGGCUGUGGCCCGCAUCUUCCACGGCAUCGGAAGCCCCUGCUACCCGGCCCAGGUGUACGGGCAGGACCGACGCUUCUGGAGAAAAUACCUGCACCUGAGCUUCCAUGCCCUGGUGGGCCUGGCCACGGAAGAGCUCCUGCAGGUGGCCCGCUGACUGCACUGCAUUGGGGGAUGUCGGGUAGAGCUGGGGUUGUCAGAGGCUAGGGCAGUGACUGAGGACCUGGGCAAAACCUGCCACAGGGUGUGGGAACGAGGAGGCUCCAAAAUGCAGAAUAAAAAAUGCUCACUUUGUUUUUA